ACUGGCGCGGGUUGAGUUCCCUGUUGCCCUUGGUCUCGGGGUCGCUGUAGGCGCUGAGGCUGCAGAGAUGUGACCCAGUGACCGCCCGCUAACCGGACUGGAGAGAAGACCGGCCCGGAUCCCACGCCUGGCCUGAAGCAGGGAAGACGCUGCCUCCCCUCCGCGAGCAGCUUACAUUCGUCCAAGUUCCAGCCUUCUGUCUUCUCGCUAACCUCGCUCUCUUCCAAAUCGCAAAUCCUCUUGAGCCGACACCGUUGCGCCUAAAUGAUCUAUCAUGGUGAACUUACUUCAGAUUGUGCGGGACCACUGGGUUCAUGUUCUUGUCCCUAUGGGAUUUGUCAUUGGAUGUUAUUUAGACAGAAAGAGUGAUGAACGGCUAACUGCCUUCCGGAACAAGAGUAUGUUAUUUAAAAGGGAAUUGCAACCCAGUGAAGAAGUUACCUGGAAGUAAAGACUGGCUAGAUUAUCGAAUGUUCACAUUUUAAAGUUCUGAGAGAAAUAAAAACAUGAAGAAUCUGAAA